UUAUUUAUUUAUUUAUUUUUUGUAGAGAAUGAGGCCUCGCUGUGUUGCCCAGGCUGGUCUCGGACUCCUGGCCUCAAGCAAUCCUCUUGCCUCGGCCUCUCAAAGUGUUGGGAUUACAGGCGUGAGCCAUUGCGCCUGGGCAGGUAUUUUUUCUCAUUAAGCGCUCCCCAUCCAAGUCUGCCCUAGGCAGGAGUGCCUAGUGCACGGGUACAUACAUACCCCGUGCGUCUCCACACCUGUGCGCUCCCACAGAUAUGCUCGCAAUGCAGGUGUAAGGUCCCCCUCACACCUGCGCGCUUCCGCGGUCUCCCUCCCCGCAUCCCCAUUAAGGGACUGGGGUCCCGUUACAGGUGCGCCCACAGCGCGGCCCCGCCCCCUUCUUGACUCCGCCCUCUCAGCGAGGCUCAGGUGCACAAGCCGGAAGUGCGCUCUCCCAGGUGCCCCGUCGCAGGUGCCCCUGGCCGGAGAUGCGGUAGGAGGGGCGAGCGCGAGAAGCCCCUUCCUCGGCGCUGCCAACCCGCCACCCAGCCCAUGGCGAACCCCGGGCUGGGGCUGCUUCUGGCGCUGGGCCUGCCGUUCCUGCUGGCCCGCUGGGGCCGAGCCUGGGGGCAAAUACAGACCACUUCUGCAAAUGAGAAUAGCACUGUUUUGCCUUCAUCCACCAGCUCCAGCUCCGAUGGCAACCUGCGUCCAGAAGCCAUCACUGCUAUCAUCGUGGUCUUCUCCCUCUUGGCUGCCUUGCUCCUGGCUGUGGGGCUGGCACUGUUGGUGCGGAAGCUUCGGGAGAAGCGGCAGACGGAGGGCACCUACCGGCCCAGUAGCGAGGAGCAGGUGGGUGCCCGCGUGCCACCGACCCCCAACCUCAAGUUGCCGCCGGAAGAGCGGCUCAUCUGAACGCUGGGGCCUGCUGCAGCCACCAACACUGCCCAGGACUGCGGGUUGCUGGCUUGUACACCGCAGCUGCCACCGAGACACCAGCCUCUGAUGGCUCAGGAGGACUUGUGGGGAGAGGCUGGGGGCACCCAUGUGGUGGGCUCUGUGCAGCAUGUUGCCUCUGCUUGGCUGUGCCUGCAGCUCAGGGUGCUGGGGCUCGGGACCCACCCCCCUGCUUGCGGAACCAACUUUUCUCUGUGUGUCCAGCAGGCCCCACAACCCCCUCUCCUUUCUUUCAGUUCUCCCAUGCAGCCGAGGCCCGGGCCCCUCAGGACUCCAAGGAGACGGUGCAGGGCUGCCUGCCCAUCUAGGUCCCCUCUCCUGCAUCUGUCUCCCUUCAUUGCUGUGUGACCUUGGGGAAAGGCAGUGCCCUCUCUGGGCAGUCAGAUCCACCCAGUGCUUAAUAGCAGGGAAGAAGGUACUUCAAAGACUCUGCCCCUGAGGUCAAGAGAGGAUGGGGCUAUUCACUUUUAUAUAUUUAUAUAAAAUUAGUAGUGAGAUGUAACAAAA